CCCUUAAGUGCAUUUAUAAUUACAUUGAUCAGCUCUGAGUUUGUGAUAUGCCAAGUCCUUGAAUGUGAUACUCAUUUGCUUUCACGUUUUUGAUGCAAAUGGAUCUUGGAAUCCAUUCUAGAGUGCUUUGGUAGAUUUUUUAAUCCACAAUAGGCAAUUUAUCUUGUUCAGCCUCUACAAGGACUGUCUGGUAUGGCCGGUCUGGGCAUCUGGCUGGCCACGAGCCUGCCCAGUAGGGACUCAGUUGGGACCUGCUGAGAGCAGUUUCACUUUCGCAUUUGCUUCCUCUUGUCCACAGCUGAACUGAGAGGUGUUCUCGGGGAUCCCUAGAGUAUUGAGAACAAAGAGCAGAAGGAAGAGCUUGCAUACUUCUAUUUUCCAUCCAUUCAGUGAAUAUUUAGUGCCUGCCCCAAGGCAGGUUUUGAGGAUACAGCAGACGGCACAACAGGCAGACAUAUCCUUGUGGACGUGCUCUGGCACCAAGCUGUUUCCAACUCAGCACAUGUGGGAAAGGAACUGGCACUUUUUUGUAUCCUUGCUAUCUUCGGCAUAUGUGGGCAUACUUAUUUAAGCCUCACAACUGUCUGUGAAGUAGGUAUUAUUAAGGGUUAUGUAGGCCACAUGUAUCUGUGAACAUCAUACUGGUGUGUGGUGUUUUGCAUAAUAGAGCUAUGAAAUUAUGCAGCUGGGGUUUGAAAAUAAACCCUGCCUUUGGCCAUCUAGAUGUUGAACAAGGGACUUAAAUGCUCACAGCCUCCUCCUCUUCCCCUGUUUUGAAUGAGGCUAAAGGUUGGACCUCUCAGGAUCAUUUGGUAGUUAACACUUUGCAAGUUGGCAUGGAUACACACAGGUAUUGUAAACCUGUGUGUGCUUGAAAAGCAGCGGCUGUUUCUGCCUGUGAUUCUGGAGUUACUUCUGGAUUUGAUCCUAUACAGAAUGCUCUUAUAUCCUGUUCAUUAUAGGGAAGGAAGCUUGUGGCAGGGAAUCUGCAGACCCACGUUCCACCUGGUUCUAUCAUCAAAUUGUGUGGUCUCGGACAAGUUCCUAGACCUCUCUAGUUCUCAGUUGUCGCAUAUCUGAAAUGAGACGAUGGUGCUGAUUUCCCUUUGGAUUAAUUUCUCCUUGGAUUAAUUUCUCUUUGGUGGCUUUGUUUAGGCCCCCCCUUCAUUUCCAUCAAGACUUUCUCAUGUUUCAGUUUCAUAUGGCGGAGGGCUUGCCUGGCUGCCUCAUUGAUCACUGUGACCCUCGCCUGGCAUUCCCAUCCCUCUUUACCCUGUUCUGUUUUUUCUUUAUUUUCAUAGCACUUAUCACUUUUCUUUCUUUCUUUCUUUCUUUUUUUUUUUUUUUUUUUUUUUGGAGACGGAGUCUCGCUGUCUUGCCCACGCUGGAGUGCAGCGGCCCAAUCUCCACUCACUGUAACCUCCGCCUCCCAGGUUCAAGCAAUUCUCCUGCCUCAGCCUCCCAAGUAGCUGGGACUACAGGUGUACGCCGCCACGCCCGGCUUAUUUUUUGUAUAUAUGUUUUUUUAGUAGAGACGGGAUUUCACUGUGUUGCCCAGGCUGGUCUCGAACUCCUGAGUUCAGGCAAUCUGCCCGCCUUGGCCUCCAAAAGUGCUAGGAUUACAAGUGUGAGCCACCGUGCCCAGCCUUUAUCGUACUUAGCACUUUCUAACAGACUGUAUGUUUUUUUAAAUUUGUUGUGUUUAUUUUUAUAGACAAAAAACACAUGUUACCUUUGCUGGAAUGUAACCUAAUUAAGGGGCGAAAUCUUUAUCGAUCUUGUGCCCAGACCACCUUGAAGCCAUGAAGGGAUGCUCAGGAGGCUUUGUUAAAUAUAAAACAAAUUCUGAAAUAAAAGUGACUAUUAAUUACUUCCACAGUUGAUGGCAGGAAAAAAAAAACUUCAUCUGGGAGCAUCGGUUUCAGUUUCUCAGCUCAGAGGCCUCUUUUUGUAGCUCCAGGGCUGACCUUUCAACGUUGGCUCACAUCAGCCUUCUCCAUCAUGAGUCUUAUUUUUAAAAAGUACAAAGUAAAUACCACAAACAGGUAUUGUGACUUGUGGAACAAGUUGUCGAGAAAAUUACAAAGAAUAGUUCCUUCUGCUGCUAUCUGCUUAGAGCCAGCCUGGCUCUAAUAGCUGGGGCCUUUGUGUGUUCUCUUCUUGGGCAUAAAGAGUUUCACAGAAUACAAUAUAGAGUGAUGGAGUCACUCUAUGUUGGUAAUAGAACAAGACAAAAACAAGACCACUCAAUCAUCAACACUGAGCACAGAUAAAAGCAAGAUCACUGCAAGGCACAAAAACAACCAAACAUUCCCCAGUCUCAGCUCACACGAAUGUUUCUUUACCGAUUAUGGCUUUAGCCUCAUUCUGUUCCUCCUGCCUCUUAGAUAAAAAUUAGGAAGCUACGUCAUCAUAAAAUUUCUGCUCUGUUGACAGCACCCAAUUCAGAGCAAAACUACAUUUCCCUGAGCCUACCCCUAAAUCACUGAACACAGUCCAAAUUGUAUAAUGAGCUCCUCCUGACAUCCUCUUGCUGAGAUCUCUGAAAUUCUGCCUGUUGUAGUGUCCACCUUGCUGCAGUGAACCAAUGAACCCAACUUUGUUUGACCACAGGUAUGUUCCUGGUAGUCUUUAACUGGAGCCGGUGGCAUAGUCGCUUGGUGAAUAAAACUUUGUCCUAGGCAUCACUGUAGAAAUGUGUAGGUUAUUUUACAGCUGAAUGGUAUUGAAUAGACAUGUACACAGUUUAAUUGGAGAGCUGAGUCACUUGAUAAUUGUGGAAACAGAGCAGGAUGUGACAGAAGGCAGAAAUGCAAAGGUUGGGUAAGUGUGCCUCGAAGUAAGUGACUUGAGAGAAGGAGAAAGCCUAGAAGGCUGGGGCGGUAGAGAGAAGGUAGCUAGGGCUGGAAGACACAGUGGGGUCUUGAGUAAAUCGCUUGUUUAGGAGUCAAGAGACCCAAGGUCUUAUCCUGGAUUUACUGCAUAUGAGCUGUUAACAAGUCCAAUUGUUAGGUUUUUCAUUUGUAAAAAACAGGGUCAGUAAUCUCUCCUCCUUAUCUCACAUGGUAGUUAACUUGUGUGAAACACCUUGUAAAGUGUCUUGUGCUGGAAAAGUGUAAGGCCUGGCUCUAAUUGUGGAGAGAAUUAAAAAACAUGCAGUUUCAAGGUGUUUCACCCAUAAGCCAGGUGCCAAAUGAUCCCUCUCUGUCUUCCACCACCCAAACUUUAGAAAUGGGGGUUGCCAUAGGAACCUUGUCAUUAUCAUUCAGCAGCUAUAGACUUGCUCAGGUGGUGUCUUUUUUUUUAAGACCGGUUAGGUUACUUAUAGGGUCUUGGGAGCAGGAGUGUGGUGGGAGGGGCAUAAGAGAGAGGCAGGGAUAGAAUUAGAAUGGGGAGCCAGCAAAACUCUUCCUCCAUCAGAUGAGGGGCCUGGGAUCCAGCUGCUACCUUUAUGCCCUCCGCCCUAUCCCCCUCCACUCUGAGUCAGACUUGGUUGUUCAAGGAUUUAAAUGGGAAAAUGUGUUAGCCAGAUUAUCCUUCCAAAUAAGGUUAUAAAGUCUACCGUAUUAAAGAGGGGAAGAUUUCCUUCUGUGGAAUUUCAGAUCUUGAUAAUAGUAAUGGUAAUAAUAAUAAUACGACUGUCUGUCAUUUAUUAGGUGUUUGUUAUAUGCUGGACACUGGAUUCAGCAUUUGUGGGUGUUGCUUCCUUUAGUACUUGCAAUAAAUUCAUUGUUAUCCUUCUUUGCAAAUGAGGAGGCGGAAACCUAGAGGUUAAAUUACCCACCCACAGUCACCAGCCAGCUGGCCUCACAGCCCAGAGUUGAACUAGGUCCCUCUGACCUCAAGUGCGGAAGACUUAAGACUCUGCUCCCUGGUUUCCUUGCAGAUAAUCCUAGGAUAUGAGAGCUAUUAUCUAGAACACUCGUCUUUUAGAUGGGAAAAUAGGGGUUAGAAGAGGUGAAAUCCCUGUUUGAAGGCCGUGUUAUUGCUGCUGCUGGUGGUAGGGCCUGGGUGUGGCCCGAGAUCUUCUGAUCCUCAGUCCAGAGAGUGAAUAGGACUUUUCUCCUGAUGGGUUUAAAUAUGAGUGGUUGUGGUCGCUGGCAGUUUCUGCAACAGAAGUAUGGUCCUCCUUUUACUUUUCUGUGGAAAAGGCCCUCAAGCUACAGAACCAGAUCAUUGCACCCCCACCCCCUACCAGCCAUCUGACCCUGGGCUCCUUCUUUAAUCUCUCCAUCCCUUUGUAUUUCCUCGUAUGGAAAAUUGGGAUAACAACUGUACCUAUACCUUAGUAUUGUAAUAAGAACUAAAGGAGUCCGGGCGCAGUGGCUCACGCCUGUAAUCCCAGUACUUUGGGAGGCAGAGGCGGGAGGAUCGCCUGAGGUCAGGAGUUUGAGACCAGCCUGGCCAACACGGUGAAACCCCGUCUGUAGUUAAAAUACAAAAAAGUUAGCUGGGCAUGGUGGUGCUCAUCUGUAAUCCCAGCUUCUUGGAAGGCUGAGGCAGGAGAAUUGCUUGAACCUGGGAGGUAGAGGUUGCAGUGAGCCAAGAUCGCACCACUGCACUCCAGCCUGGACAACAGACUGAGACUCUGUCUCAAAAAAAAAAAAAAAAAAAAAAAAGAGAAGAAAAGAAAAAAGAACUAAAGGGAUUAAUAUGUUGAAAACUCAUAGCCUGGUGUCUAGUACCCAGUAGGUUAUGAGUGAGUACUGCCUGUUAAUAAUGUAUCGCAUCCCUCGUUUGAAGGAUGUAGUCCUAAUUUGAGUUUUUUUCAGUAGACUGGAGCUCCUGCCCUCACCCUAUAGCAUUCGUAUCCUCUGAGAUACAUGGAUACUGUUGAAGUUAUGGUGAAGAUGAUGGGGUGCUGGGAGGUGGAGUGGAAUGGGAUUGAUUGAUGAAAAAACGACAUUAGCUUGCUAAGGACACCCAGGUGGUUGAGAUGUUCUGCGAAGUGGGCCUGUGUGUCUGCUGGACCUGGAGUUGAGGGGACAGCUUUCUUCUGAGGCAGCGUCUUAUCCUGGGGUGACUCCGGGAGGCAAAAGCAUUAACUAUUGAUGAGACUGAUGACACACUAUCAUUCCUAGACCAGAAAUGGUGCAAGAACAGAGAGGAUUUAUCCUGCUCUUCUUUCUCUACACAGUCCCUGUGUCAGAGAAGGUGUCUGCUGAGUGGACAGGCCAAGAACUGUUCUCUGGGACGGAGUGCAGAUGAAGUAGGGGGUGUAAACCCAUGAAGAACAAUGAAGCAGAGCGAGUGAAGCAGGACAGGCUGGGGUGGAGGAGAAAGAAUUUGCCUUUAUUGUGCAAUUAGCCUUUUCGAUUCUUUAAAAGCUUUAGGAGAUAGUGAAUAUGUCCCUCCAAUCUACAGACCCGAAGAGGCAUCUCGGGAAAGUGAUUUGCCCAGGGGGACAGAUCAAGGACCUGACCCCAGGUCCCUCUCUCUGCCUCAGAGGCCCUCUGGGAUCCAUUAAAGGGUCUUGUCUUGAGUAAUUAACUGAAUACUGGUUUAUUCAGAAUGAGGGGUCUUUAAUUGGGGGAUAGGCAUACCUUUGGUAAAACCACUGGAGUUUUUGGGCCCAGUGUCUGGCAGUGUGCAAGGAGCGUGGGGCAUCUUUGGCACAACGCGGCUUCAGGAAGAGCCCUCCUUCCCUUCCUGAGUAAGGCAGAGUUUGAGUCAGGCUGGGGUGGGCUCCUGGUGUGGGGACAGGUUAUUGUGGGUGCUGGAGGGAAUGACUUUCACUCUGAGUCAUUCAGUGGCCUGCAGGGGUGCAGGGCUGGGGGUGGAGAGAGAAAUAGAGGGCUGGCCAAAGACUCUCAGUGCCUGCCCUUUCUUACCCCUAGGGCCCAUGAGCCUGGUUUAAAAACCGCUUAUCCACCACCUCGUUUUCAUUCUCACACACUGAGUCCUUUAGACGUAAGCCUGUUGGUGAGGAAGACUGUUGCAGUGGCUGAGAUGUGCUGGGCGAAAGAUUUUCAACUAGUCUUUUCCUAAUAAGCACCUACUUGUUUAUAUUCUGAGCUUUCACAGCAGCAUUCUAGAAAAAAGAAAUACGGAGGACUCAAAAAAAAUACGCUGCCUGAUUUAGUUUUGAUUGCUCACGUCUCUGGCUUCUUUCAUGGAACUAUUAAUUGACUAUAGGGAGUAGCUGCUUUUCGCACAAUAAGCUCCUAGUCAUGAAGCAAAAUGGUGACAUUGAUCAUUUUGGGGUCCCUCAGACUCUGGCAACGUUGAAACAGGCUGUCAGUUUUUUUUGUAACCACCAGUUAGCAUGAGUGGGGGUGGCAGAAAUUACCAGUUUGAUUUUUGAUCAGGGGCUAUGGCUUAUACUUAAGCUAUUUGGAGGGAGGAGAAAGCGUGAAUGAGCGAGUUAAGGCAGUAGAAAGAUGGAGCCAUGCUGGGUUUUUAGGCAGUUGUUUCAAAAACAACACAAAGUGAGAAAUGGUGAAAACCAGGAACUGUUUGGCUUUUUCUAGUUUACAAUGAGAGAAGAAAGAUGUUUGGGGAAUUUUAGAAGACUUGAGUCUAUCGUGUAGUACAUCUGGUGGAGUCCUUGUACAGAUGCCUGUGUUAUCAUAAAAGGGGAACCACCAUAGAUUCUGUUUUAAAACUUUCUACAAAUUGUAUGUGUUGAUAUUAACUUCUGCAGAUGGAGAGAGGAAAAGAGGAAAAGAGUAUUAUGAGGGAGGCCGAGGACUUCAUGCUCCGGACAGAGAAACGGCGCUGGGAUUAGGGAUUGCCACUUCUGAGAGGAUGCUGGGAAUCUGCAGGGGGAGACGGAAAUUCUUGGCUGCCUCGUUGAGUCUUCUCUGCAUCCCAGCCAUCACCUGGAUUUACCUGUUUUCUGGGAGCUUCGAAGAUGGAAAGCCCGUGUCUCUGUCACCGCUGGAGUCCCAGGCACACAGCCCCAGGUACACGGCCUCCAGCCAGCGGGAGCGCGAGAGCCUGGAGGUGCGCAUGCGCGAGGUGGAGGAGGAGAACCGCGCCCUCCGCAGGCAGCUCAGCCUGGCCCAGGGCCGAGCCCCAUCCCAUCGCCGAGGCAACCACUCCAAGACCUACUCCAUGGAGGAGGGCACUGGAGACAGCGAGAACCUUCGGGCUGGCAUCGUGGCAGGCAACAGCUCCGAGUGUGGGCAGCAGCCGGUCGUGGAGAAAUGCGAGACAAUCCACGUUGCUAUUGUCUGCGCCGGAUACAAUGCCAGCCGGGAUGUCGUCACCCUGGUCAAAUCCGUCCUGUUCCAUAGACGGAACCCUCUGCACUUCCACCUUAUUGCUGACUCCAUUGCGGAGCAGAUCCUGGCCACGCUCUUCCAGACCUGGAUGGUGCCCGCUGUGCGUGUGGACUUCUACAAUGCAGACGAGCUCAAGUCUGAAGUUUCCUGGAUCCCCAAUAAACAUUACUCUGGGAUUUAUGGUCUGAUGAAGCUUGUCCUGACCAAGACUCUUCCUGCCAACCUGGAGAGAGUCAUCGUCCUUGACACGGAUAUCACCUUUGCCACUGACAUUGCAGAGCUGUGGGCUGUGUUCCACAAGUUCAAAGGUCAGCAAGUCCUGGGCUUGGUGGAGAACCAGAGUGACUGGUACCUUGGAAACCUGUGGAAAAAUCACCGCCCAUGGCCAGCCCUUGGAAGAGGCUACAACACAGGGGUGAUCCUGUUACUUCUGGAUAAGCUGCGGAAGAUGAAAUGGGAGCAGAUGUGGAGGCUGACCGCAGAGAGGGAGCUCAUGGGCAUGCUCUCUACAUCCUUAGCUGACCAGGAUAUUUUCAAUGCCGUCAUCAAACAAAACCCCUUCCUUGUGUACCAGCUCCCCUGCUUCUGGAAUGUGCAGCUGUCAGACCACACCCGCUCCGAGCAGUGCUACAGAGACGUGUCUGAUCUAAAGGUCAUUCACUGGAACUCCCCCAAGAAGCUCCGGGUGAAGAACAAGCAUGUGGAGUUUUUUCGCAACCUCUACCUGACCUUCCUGGAGUAUGACGGCAAUCUUCUGAGGCGGGAACUGUUUGGCUGCCCCAGUGAGGCUGAUGUCAACAGUGAAAACCUCCAGAAGCAGCUGUCUGAGCUGGACGAGGACGACCUGUGCUAUGAGUUCCGGCGAGAGCGCUUCACUGUCCACCGCACCCACCUGUACUUCCUGCACUACGAGUAUGAGCCUGCAGCAGACAGCACGGACGUCACCCUGGUCGCUCAGCUGUCCAUGGACAGGCUCCAGAUGCUGGAGGCCAUCUGCAAGCACUGGGAGGGGCCCAUCAGCCUGGCCCUCUACCUGUCAGACGCCGAGGCCCAGCAGUUCCUCCGCUACGCACAGGGCUCUGAGGUGCUUAUGAGCCGCCACAACGUGGGCUACCACAUCGUGUACAAGGAGGGCCAGUUCUACCCCGUGAACCUGCUGCGCAACGUGGCCAUGAAGCACAUCAGCACUCCCUACAUGUUCCUGUCUGACAUUGACUUCCUGCCCAUGUAUGGGCUCUAUGAGUACCUCAGGAAGUCUGUCAUCCAGCUCGAUCUUGCCAACACCAAGAAAGCAAUGAUUGUCCCCGCGUUCGAGACACUGCGCUACCGGCUGUCCUUCCCCAAGUCAAAAGCGGAGUUGCUGUCAAUGCUGGACAUGGGGACCCUCUUCACAUUCAGGUACCACGUCUGGACGAAAGGCCACGCACCCACAAACUUCGCCAAGUGGCGGACCGCCACCACGCCUUACCGGGUUGAGUGGGAGGCCGAUUUUGAGCCGUAUGUUGUUGUGAGACGUGACUGCCCGGAGUACGACCGGAGGUUUGUAGGCUUUGGCUGGAACAAAGUGGCUCAUAUCAUGGAGCUGGAUGUGCAGGAGUAUGAGUUCAUUGUGCUGCCCAACGCCUACAUGAUCCACAUGCCUCAUGCCCCCAGCUUCGACAUUACCAAGUUCCGUUCCAACAAGCAAUACCGCAUCUGUCUCAAAACCCUCAAGGAAGAGUUUCAGCAGGACAUGUCCCGCCGCUACGGCUUUGCUGCCCUGAAAUAUCUCACAGCCGAGAACAACAGCUAGCACCAAGAAGCCCACCACUAGGGGGAGACAUGCUGUAGGGGAAGUGCCACUCGCUGUUUGGGGCCCGGCCUUCAAAUUCAAAAUUGAGCCAUGCUUUUUCGGUUUGUUUUUAUUUAUCUCUUUGGCCCAGCCAAGCUGCCCUCACUACAGAGACCUUGGACAAGGAUCCAGCCAGUCCCUCUCUGCCCCACAACCCUGCAUUCCCAGAGGUUAGCUAUGCAGCCCACCUAGAUGAGUCUCUUCAAGAAUGGGAAAUCAAGGGGUGACAGGGAGUAAAAGGGUUAUCAUCUUACUGCAAAGCCACAAGAUCAGGGCAGGGCUUUAGGAUGUUCUGGAUGCUUUUUAAUAAUUAUGCUUCCCAUCAUAACUGGGGAGAAAGGGAAGUCAGGGUUCUAGGGGUUAUUCGUCCCAGGAAAUAGAAGUGAAAUUGUCUUUAUUAAGUGAAAACUUUCCCCUUUGCCCUGCAAUGUAGCUGGGCAUUCAAACGGAGGGCAAACCGAUGAUCUAAACCAACCACUUGGAAAAACCCAAUGGGGACAUUGUAACCAGAGGGUCCUGGAGGUGGGGUUGAUGGGUUUCCUUAUCCCCAAAGUCACUCCUGUUUUGUUUUGUUUUUCUUUGGGGGUUUUGUUUAUUUUUGGGGCUGGCAAUCCAAAAUAGAAAAUCUGAUCCUUUGAGGCUCUAAAGGAAAAUCAGCUGCCUCUACCAACCACCCUCUAUCAGCAGUGGCCCAGGAAGGAGGUCAAGCAUCUUCGGCCGAUAUUUAAACAUGGGCAGCUUCCUUCAGGAUGAUCACCGAGGCUCCCGUGACUUUGAACUCCCUACUCUCCAGAAUCCAGGGGCUAUAGCGAUGGGGACUGCGGAAUUACGAGGGCUGGCUGUUUUACACCGGUCACAUUUUCUAUUGGCAGUGACUGAUUCAUGGGAAAGGGCUUUGAAGGAACUACUUCAGUGCACACACAAGGUACGAACCUCUCAGGCCUUUCGAAGAACUUUCAUAAUUCAUGAAAGCCCAGUUCUGAAGAUUCACGUAUCCAUCUGGAGACCUACAGGAAGAAAGUGAUUGGGUUCCUCUGGUUCUUGCCUGCUUCACUGUGGAUGGGAAGAGGUGACAACCUCAGUCUCCCUUUGGGACCUGUCCAAGGGUAGGCAACCACCUUCACCUUCACACAGAUUGAGGAGACACUGGACUUUUUACCCAUUUUCUUUAAUCUUCAAUAUUAAUAUUGUGUUUACAUUGAUGAGAACAAGAGUUAAUGCCCUACCCUCUGCUGGGCUGUUUGUAUUGAGUUGCAAUGUGACCAGCGAAAGCUGCAUUUAAUAAAUGAAAGUACAGACUGUUUCUUCCCCAUUCCCCUCCCACUCUUGCAGGAAGCUACUGAGACACACCUUGACAUAGAGAGCUAAAUUGCAGUGGAUAAACAGCAACUUCACACUUUCUGUUCCCCCAUUCUAUUUUUCUCAUCAUUUGAACUUUAGCCUUUUUUUUCCCCUUUUGCCUGAAGUUAGAUCCCACUCUGUCUCUAACUCAAACCAUCUUCAAGUUUUCCAUUCCGCAUCUUUCUCAACACUGGAGCCAGAUGUUGUCUUCUACCAGAUGUGGGCUAGGAGGGUAAAUCCUGGUAAUCAAUUGUAAAGGGAACAUCCCAUCCUUGGGCCUGGUAGUCAUGUGGGACCCUAUAGCAAUCCGGUUUGUGAGAUCACUCACGAUGUUACAUGCUCAAGUGGAUGUUACACGGAAAUUUAUACAAGAAUUAGGAAAAUUACCAUUAGGACUAAUUUUUGCAUAGAUCUAGCUAGGCUUAUGUAUGUAUGUAAAUAUAUAUGUAGACAGAGCAUACAAGUAUAUAGCCUAUAUACAAAGCAUUUAUAAAUAAAAAGUGACAUAUAUGUAUAAAGCAGAACAAAAAUUUUGAAA